CUCUUACCGCCCUUUUCCGGGGCAAGGGAAGCUAGUAGCGGAGCCGGAAGUGAGGCACCCUCGGGCUCGAGACAGCGGCGACGUUUAAAGCUGAGCGACCCAGUGCCACUGGAGACGGUCAGCUUCUCCACUCAGGCUCCUCCAGCCCGAGCCAGAAGACCCCCUCCCCCAGAAUUCUGGGGGCCGAUGGAAGGGAGCCGAGUCAGAUCGCGAGGUACCCAGAGCCGACAGACCGGAGCGACAGGGAGUUGCCAGAAGCCCCGCCCCUAGGAGUGAUCGGAAAGCCUCACCCAUCCGGGUGAGGAACCCGGAGGGACCGCCUCCGGGCGGAGCCCGCCGACCAUGGCUACGCCCCUGGUGGCGGGUCCCGCAGCUCUACGCUUCGCCGCCGCGGCUAGCUGGCAGGUUGUGCGCGGACGCUGCGUGGAACAUUUUCCGCGAGUACUGGAGUUUCUGCGAUCUCUGCGCGCUGUUGCCCCUGGCUUGGUUCGCUACCGGCACCACGAACGCCUUUGUAUGGGCCUAAAGGCCAAGGUGGUGGUGGAGCUGAUCCUGCAGGGCCGGCCUUGGGCCCAAGUCCUGAAAGCCCUGAAUCACCACUUUCCAGAAUCUGGACCUAUAGUGCGGGAUCCCAAGGCUACAAAGCAGGAUCUGAGGAAGAUUUUGGAGGCACAGGAAACUUUUUACCAGCAGGUGAAGCAGCUGUCAGAGGCUCCUGUGGAUUUGGCCUCGAAGCUGCAGGAACUUGAACAAGAGUAUGGGGAACCCUUUCUGGCUGCCAUGGAAAAGCUGCUUUUUGAGUACUUGUGUCAGCUGGAGAAAGCACUGCCUACACCGCAGGCACAGCAGCUUCAGGAUGUGCUGAGUUGGAUGCAGCCUGGAGUCUCUAUCACCUCUUCUCUUGCCUGGAGACAAUAUGGUGUGGACAUGGGGUGGCUGCUUCCAGAGUGCUCUGUUACUGACUCAGUGAACCUGGCUGAGCCCAUGGAACAGAAUCCUCCUCAGCAACAAAGACUAGCACUCCACAAUCCCCUGCCAAAAGCCAAGCCUGGCACACAUCUUCCUCAGGGACCAUCUUCAAGGACGCACCCAGAACCUCUAGCUGGCCGACACUUCAAUCUGGCCCCUCUAGGCCGACGAAGAGUUCAGUCCCAAUGGGCCUCCACUAGGGGAGGCCAUAAGGAGCGCCCCACAGUCAUGCUGUUUCCCUUUAGGAAUCUCGGCUCACCAACCCAGGUCAUAUCUAAGCCUGAGAGCAAGGAAGAACAUGCGAUAUACACAGCAGACCUAGCCAUGGGCACAAGAGCAGCCUCCACUGGGAAGUCUAAGAGUCCAUGCCAGACCCUGGGGGGAAGGGCUCUGAAGGAGAACCCAGUUGACUUGCCUGCCACAGAGCAAAAGGAGUGAGUGGAACAGAGUUGCUUCUUACUAGGAGCACAUUCUUUGCCUGCCUUCCCUUCAUCCUAUCCUCUUUGCUUGCUCUCACCUCAGGAAUUGCUUGGAUUGCUACAUGGACCCCCUGAGACUAUCAUUAUUACCUCCUAGGGCCAGGAAGCCAGGUAGGUAGUCUGAGUCAGGAUUGGAUCAACAGCCUCCUCUCUUGGGGACUCUCAAGAGCCUGUGUUCAUCUAGAAGUAGUAGUUUGAUUCUGGUUUCCCUCCUACAGUGUGUCCUCCGUCUCUGUGCAGCUCCGUCAUUACCAUAGGGGACUUGGUUUUAGACUCUGAUGAGGAAGAAAAUGGCCAGGGGGAAGGAAAGGUGAGUGGGAAGGAGCAGAAAGCUGGGAAAGGGGAUGGGUAGAACAAGACUGAGAAAUCCACAUGCUUCAGAAUUCAGAGGGUUCAGGGAAUGGUUUCGGAUAGUAGGCUCUCCCUGCUCCCUUCUCUACAGGAAUCUCUGGAAAACUAUCAGAAGACAAAGUUUGACACCUUGAUACCCACUCUCUGUGAAUACCUACCCCCUUCUGGCCACGGUGCCAUACCUGUUUCUUCCUGUGACUGUAGAGACAGUUCUAGACCUUUGUGAUAGAACUAAAAUGCUCUCUGUACUCUAGUCUCCUGCCUCCUCAGCUCUGCAAGUAGUUUAGUAGGAAUGAAGUGGAAGUCCAGGCUUGGAUUGCCUAACUACACUGCUAAAAAUAUUUGUAAUCCUUAAUAAUUAAACUUUGGAUUUGUUAAAAUAC